ACUCUUUCCUGCUGCCUAGUCUGCUGAGCAGAGCUUCAGUCUCCACCAUCAAUCAUCCAGUGAGGAAUUUGCACUUACACAAGGAACUCUUCCUCGGAGAGAUCCCCUCCUGAGAUGGAGUUUCACCACGUUGUCCAGGCUGGUCUCGAACUCCUGGGCUCAAGCAAUUUACUUGCCUCAGCCUCCCAAAGUGCUAGGAUUGCAGACGUGUGCCACCACGCCCAGCCUAGAUGGCGUUUCGCCAUAUUGCCCAGGCUGGUCUUGAACUCCCGACCUCAAGUGAUCCACCCACCUGGACCUUCCAAACUGCUGGGAUUACAGGCAUGAGCCACCGUACCUGGCCGAUAUUGAAGUUUUUAAUUCCUCUGACUUUGUGUAAGAUGUGUGAGUCACUUCAAUCAAAUGGAACCAGGAAAUGAUACACAAAUUUCAGAAUUUCUUCUUCUGGGAUUUUCACAAGAACCUGGACUGCAACCCUUCCUCUUUGGGCUGUUCCUGUCCAUGUACCUGGUCACUGUGCUCGGGAACCUGCUCAUCAUCCUGGCCACAAUCUCAGACUCCCACCUCCACACCCCCAUGUACUUCUUCCUCUCCAACCUGUCCUUUGCUGACAUUUGUGUUACUUCCACCACCAUUCCAAAAAUGCUGAUGAACAUCCAGACACAGAACAAAGUCAUCACCUACAUAGCCUGCCUCAUGCAGAUGUAUUUUUUCAUACUCUUUGCUGGAUUUGAAAACUUCCUCCUGUCCGUGAUGGCCUAUGACCGGUUUGUGGCCAUCUGUCACCCCCUGCACUACAUGGUCAUUAUGAACCCUCACCUCUGUGGACUGCUGGUUCUAGCAUCCUGGACCAUGAGUGCUCUGUAUUCCUUGCUACAAAUCUUAAUGGUAGUACGGCUGUCCUUCUGCACAGCCUUAGAAAUCCCCCACUUUUUCUGUGAACUUAAUCAGGUCAUCCAACUUGCUUGUUCUGAUAGCUUUCUUAAUCACAUGGUGAUAUAUUUUACAGUUGCGCUGCUGGGUGGAGGUCCCCUGACUGGGAUCCUUUACUCUUACUCUAAGAUAAUUUCUUCCAUACAUGCAAUCUCAUCAGCUCAGGGGAAGUACAAGGCAUUUUCCACCUGUGCAUCUCACCUCUCAGUUGUCUCCUUAUUUUAUGGUGCAAUCCUAGGGGUGUACCUUAGUUCUGCUGCCACCCGCAACUCACACUCAAGUGCAACAGCCUCAGUGAUGUACACUGUGGUCACCCCCAUGCUGAACCCCUUUAUCUAUAGUCUGAGGAAUAAAGACAUAAAGAGGGCUCUGGGAAUACAUUUGUUGUGGGGAACAAUGAAAGGGCAAUUUUUCAAGAAGUGCCCAUGAUUGCAGGGCUCUAAGCUUCAGAGGUAGUAACUGUCAUUCUUCAAUCAGAUAGUGGAAAUAGAACUUGCUCCUUCUAUUAAUACUUAUUAUAUUUCUGGGAGUUUCAAUUUGUUGUGAUUUCAACUGGUCUUGUAGAAUUUAAGCAACUCCUUUUAUUAAGCUUUCUGCUCUCUGAUAUCCAACAGUUUUUUCUCUUUGUUGUUUUCCUACUUUCUCAAGGUUAUUUCCGACUUUGGAUCAGAAACACUUUGGAGAUUUCCAUUUGUCUCAUACAGGGAAGAGUUGUAUGUCUCCUGUGGCAUAGACUACACUUGGCAAUUGGGGUAAUUGAUGUAAAUUUAUAGUGGAAUAUGACCUGAGACCACAAUUUGUUCACUUUUGUAUUCUUCAGUCCUAUGUCUGUCUCUACCUUCAAUGCUCCUCCUGAUAAUGUAGACCUGAACAUACUUGUGUAUUUUGCAGCUGGUCAUGAGAUUGUGUUGUCCUCAUUAGGACAUCAUGUCUUUGUCAGUGCCAUGUCCACAGUAUCUGCCAUACUCCCUGGCAUAGUACGGUAAGGCAAAAAUUGUUUAUCAAAAAUAUGUUCCGAGUGCAAUGCCCACUGAAAGACAAACUUGCAUAUGUUGAUUAACUUAAUAUGGACUUACAGUCAGAGAUGACCUUAAAUAUGAUGGAGUAAAAUUGUCAAUCAUACAUUGAAUUGCUAUGGAAGACUUGUUUUUAUGAUGUGCAUGGACUCAUUGAAGUAUGGAAGCUUAGUGCCCAUAUAUAAGUUUAUUUAUUGGAGUGAUGGAUUUGGUGCCAUGGUCUAUAAUGUUUCAUGCAUCCAUACUUCUGUUUUUGCUUCAAAAUUUUUAGUGCUCCCUACAAAUACGAAUCCUUCUAUCCCACUAACCAAAAUACCUCCUUCAUUAUAAAAUUUUGUCGUAAACAUUAAAGUGCAGGUCAGUGAACAAUAUUCAAUGUAUCAUCAAUUUAUUCAUCUCUUUUAUGCUCUAAAUUCUCUUAAAUACUCAUGAUUAAAGAAUGACUCACACAAAA